AUGGGUGCCAAGAACAAUGUGACUGAGUUUGUUUUAUUUGGCCUUUUUGAGAGCAGAGAGAUGCAGCAUACAUGCUUUGUGGUAUUCUUCCUCUUUCAUGUGCUCACUGUCCUGGGGAACCUUCUGGUCAUCAUCACCAUCAAUGCUAGAAAGACCCUGAAGUCUCCCAUGUAUUUCUUCCUGAGCCAGUUGUCUUUUGCUGACAUAUGUUAUCCAUCCACUACCAUACCCAAGAUGAUUGCUGACACUUUUGUGGAGCAUAAGAUCAUCUCCUUCAAUGGCUGCAUGACCCAGCUCUUUUCUGCCCACUUCUUUGGUGGCACUGAGAUCUUCCUCCUUACAGCCAUGGCCUAUGACCGCUAUGUGGCCAUCUGUAGGCCCCUGCACUACACAGCCAUCAUGGAUUGCCGGAAGUGUGGCCUGCUAGCGGGGGCCUCCUGGUUAGCUGGCUUCCUGCAUUCCAUCCUGCAGACCCUCCUCACGGUUCAGCUGCCUUUUUGUGGGCCCAAUGAGAUAGACAACUUCUUCUGUGAUGUUCAUCCCCUGCUCAAGUUGGCCUGUGCAGACACCUACAUGGUAGGUCUCAUCGUGGUGGCCAACAGCGGUAUGAUUUCUUUAGCAUCCUUUUUUAUCCUUAUCAUUUCCUAUGUUAUCAUCUUACUGAACCUAAGAAGCCAGUCAUCUGAGGACCGGCGUAAGGCUGUCUCCACAUGUGGCUCACACGUAAUCACUGUCCUUUUGGUUCUCAUGCCCCCCAUGUUCAUGUACAUUCGUCCCUCCACCACCCUGGCUGCUGACAAACUUAUCAUCCUCUUUAACAUUGUGAUGCCACCUUUGCUGAACCCUUUGAUCUAUACACUAAGGAACAACGAUGUGAAAAAUGCCAUGAGGAAGCUGUUUAGGGUCAAGAGGAGCUUAGGGGAGAAGUGA